GUCUCUAUCUGCGGCCGGAGCUCCAGGUCUCGUCCUCACUACUCUGUGUCUUCUGCUUUUAGGGGCGCAGCCUCUGUGGCCCUGUGACCUGCCCCCUGGAAGCCUAGAAAUGGGACUGUUGACAUUUAGGGAUGUGGCCAUAGAAUUCUCUCUGGAGGAGUGGCAGUGCCUGGACACUGCACAGAAGAAUUUAUAUAGGAAUGUGAUGUUAGAGAACUACAGAAACCUGGCCUUCCUGGGUAUUGCUGUCUCUAAGCCAGACCUCAUCAUCUGUCUGGAGAAAGAAAAAGAGCCCUGGAAUAUGAAGCGAGAUGAGAUGGUGGAUGAACCCCCAGAUGGAGUCUCGCUCUGUCACCCAGGCUGGAGUGCAGUGGCGUGAUCUUGGCUCACUGCAACCUCCGCCUCCCAGGUUCAAGCCAUUCUCCUGCCUCAGCCUCCUGAGUAGCUGGGACUAUAGGUGCCGACACCGCGCUUGGCUAAUUUUUUGUAUUUUUAGUAGAAACGGGGUUUCACCGUGCUCUCGAUCUCCUGAUCUCGUGAUCUGCCCGCCUCGGCCUCCCAAAGUGCUGGGAUUACAGAUGCCAGUAAUUUAAAAUGCCUGCCUUCCAUGAAUGCACAGUUACAGUCAAACAUUGCAGUUAUCUAGACAAAUUAUUUGUUAAUGUACAUAAAUGUUGCCAACUAGUUGUAAUGAGUAAACAUUUCUGUUAUUGUGUUGCAGUUUUAUAUUAGUGUUUUUUGUAGUGUAAGUUUCCUAACAUCAGUUUAUUGUGCCUAUUGGUUUUUUCUUAUAUAUUAUGUUUUGUAUACUUUAAGUUAAUGUGGAGUUUAAUUAAAAGAUAAAUGAGCCAUGUCUAUCACAGUCAAAUUAUAUAUAUGUGUGUGUGUUUAUAUCUAUAAAUAUGACCCCAAUUUUGGUUAUACCUUGUAUAUAUUCUUUCUUAGCUCUUUUUUUUUUUUCUUUGAGAGGAAGUUUUACUCUUGUUGCCGAGGCUGAAGUGUAAUGCACGAUCUUGACUCACUGCAACCUCUGUCUCCCGGGUUCAAGUAAUUCUCCUGCCUCAGCCUCCUGAGUAGCUGGGAUUACAGGCACAUGCCACCACACCUGGCUAAUUUUGUAUUUUUUUUUUUUUUUUAGUAGAAAUGGUAUUUCUCCAUGUUGGUCAGGCUGGUCUCAAACUCCUGACCUCAGUUGAAAUGCCCACCUUGGCCUCUGAAAGUGCUGGGAUUACAGGCGUGAGCCGCCUUGCCUGGCCUCUUAGCUCAUUUUCAAUGUUGGUUUUAUCUUGUCUAAGUUAGUAGCCUUGGAAAUAGUCUUAUUUUCACCAUGUGUUUAAUGAUGAAUAUAUAUUUCCUUUGUGUGAGAUAAUUCUUUUGUGAUUUGAAGGUAAUUUUUAAAAAAGAUUCAUAAUCCUGUAUUGUCUCCAGUUUUUUAAAAAAUAAUUGUUUUAAAAAAACAUAACAUAUAAUUUACCUUCUUAAAUCCAUUUAAAUGUACAUGUCAGGGCGAGGCAAUGUGGUGGAUCCCUUCUGUAAAACCAGGAUUUUGAGAGGCCGGGACAGGAGGUUUGCUUGAGCCCAAAAGAUUGAGACCAACCUGGGUAAAAUAUGGAGACACCCUCUCUACAGAUAUUUUUUUCUAAGAAAUAGCAAGGCAUGGUGGUGUGCACCUGUGGUCCCAGCUACUUGAGAGUUUGAGGGUCAGGAUUACUUGACGCUGGGAGUGUGAGGCUGCAGUGAGCCAUAAUUGUCCCAUUGUACUCAAACUUGGGUGACAGAUUGAGACCUUGUCUUAAAAAAAAAAAAGUGUAUAUUUCAGGCAUAUCAUGUAUAUUCACAUUGUUAUGCAAAAGACUUCUAGAAAUUUUACAUCUUGUAAAACUAAAACUCAAUAUCCAUUAAAUAACAUUUACCCAUUUUAUGCUCUCUUUAGCCCUUGAGAAGCACUUUUCCACUUUCUGUUUUUACAAGUGUAAUUGUCUUAUAUAUCUAAGUGAAAUCGUAACAUCCAUCAUUUCUUUACUGGUUUAUUUCAGUUGGCAUAAUAUUCUCAAAGUGUAUCUUCAAAUGUGACGAUUUUUUUCAAGGCUGAAUAAUAUUCCAUUGUAUCAAAUAUGUCUUCAGGUUCCUAUGUUAUGUAUUUUAGAUAUAGAUUCAUAAAUGGAAUCACUUUAUUUAAUAAUUUAUAUUAUUUGAAGUACAUUUAUAACAUUAUAAAAUAAUUGGUACAUCUUUAUUUUCCACCGACAAUCAACCCAACUAACUUUUGUAUUUUUAGUAGAGACGGGAUUUCACCAUGUUGGUCAGGCUGGUCUCAAACUCCUGACGUCAGGAUUCACCCACCUCUGCCUCCCAAAGUGCUGGGAUUACAGGCUUGAGCCACCACGCCCGGCCAAGGGUUUUAUUUUUAUUGCAUCAUCAACAGAUUUGGUGUUUUCAAAAAAUUGAUAGUGGCCAUUUAAAUGAGUGUGAGGGGAUUUUGUUUUUUAUUAUGACUUUUAUGCAUUUCUCUACAAAUUAGUUUUGAGUGUCCUUUCAAAUUUUUGAAGAAAAUUUAUUUCAAUUUGUCUAUUUCUAAAUAAAGUUAUUCAAUUUGA